ACCAGUUCGCGCUCUCCUCCGGCAGAAGUAGCAGCUGCGCUCUUGCUCUCUGGGGGAGAACCUGGCGUUAUGGCCACUCAGUCAGACAUGGAGAAGGAGCAGAAGCACCAGCAGGACGAGGGGCAGGGAGGGCUGAACAACGAAACCGCCCUUGCCUCCGGGGAUGCCUGCGGGACCGGGAAUCAAGAUCCUGCUGCUUCCGUCACCACAGUCUCCAGCCAAGCAUCUCCCUCGGGCGGCGCCGCCCUAAGCAGCAGCACAGCCGGUUCUUCCGCUGCAGCCGCCACCUCCGCCGCCAUUUUCAUCACCGAUGAGGCCUCGGGGCUGCCAAUCAUAGCUGCUGUGCUGACGGAGAGGCAUUCUGACCGCCAGGACUGCCGCAGUCCUCACGAAGUUUUUGGGUGUGUGGUGCCCGAGGGGGGCAGCCAGGCCGCUGUGGGGCCCCAGAAGGCCACUGGCCACGCCGACGAGCACCUGGCCCAGACCAAGAGCCCCGGGAACAGCCGUCGUAGGAAGCAGCCCUGCCGCAACCAGGCUGCCCCGGCUCAGAAGCCUCCAGGGCGGCGUCUGUUUCCUGAGCCUUUGCCGCCAUCUUCUCCAGGGUUCCGGCCCAGCAGCUAUCCCUGUUCCGGGGCUUCUACGUCGAGUCAGGCAACCCAGCCAGGCCCUGCACUCCUAAGCCACGCAUCUGAGGCAAGGCCUGCUACCCGAAGCCGCAUCACCCUGGUAGCUUCUGCUCUCCGCAGACGUGCAUCUGGUCCAGGCCCUGUCAUCCGAGGCUGCACCGCCCAGCCAGGCCCUGCUUUUCCACACCGCGCCACUCAUCUAGACCCUGCUCGUCUAAGCCCUGAAUCUGCGCCAGGCCCUGCCCGCCGAGGCCGUGCAUCUGUGCCAGGCCCUGCCCGCCGAGGCUGCGAUUCUGCGCCAGGCCCUGCCCGCCGAGGCCGCGAUUCUGCGCCAGUCUCUGCCCCCCGAGGCCGCGAUUCUGCGCCAGGCUCUGCCCGCCGAGGCCGCGAUUCUGCGCCAGGCCCUGCCCUUCGCGUCCGCACAGCAAGGUCAGACGCCGGUCAUCGCAGCACCAGCACGACGCCAGGCACUGGCCUCCGGAGCCGUUCCACCCAGCAAAGAUCAGCCCUUCUCAGCCGCCGCUCUCUGUCUGGGUCAGCUGAUGAGAAUCCUUCCUGUGGGACUGGCUCAGAAAGGCUUGCCUUUCAGAGCAGAUCAGGCUCUCCUGAUCCUGAGGUCCCAAGCCGUGCUUCCCCGCCUGUUUGGCAUGCAGUCCGUAUGCGUGCCUCCUCACCCUCACCCCCUGGGAGGUUCUUCCUUCCCAUCCCUCAGCAGUGGGAUGAGAGCUCCUCCUCCUCCUAUGCUUCCAACUCCUCCUCCCCGAGUAGGUCUCCUGGCCUAAGCCCCUCAUCCCCUUCCCCUGAGUUUUUGGGCCUGAGAUCUAUCUCCACUCCUAGCCCUGAAAGCCUUAGGUAUGCUUUGAUGCCUGAGUUUUAUGCUCUGAGCCCUGUCCCUCCAGAAGAGCAGGCAGAAAUAGAGAGCACAGCUCACCCCGCAACACCGCCUGAGCCGUGACCCUCUAUAAGCAUCCUCUAAGACCCACAGAAGGAAUCAACAUUUACCCACUUUGUGAAUGGGCUGCCUGCCCUGUAGUUAGCUGCGAGGUCUCCCAAAGUUCCAGCCGUUAACCAACAUCCUGAGUAGUUUAGAAGCCUCUCCUCCCCAUGACUCCACCACCUAGCACUUAACCUGCUGUUGGCCUUUGAUUCUGGGCCACCUUCUUCCUCAAGAGUUUGCCUUUGCCCUUGAGCUGAGAUUUCUGUUUUCCAAGUUGCUUUUCUGUUAUGAAAUGUUUUAAUUAGUAAAAUAAAUUGUUUUGUUUAAACAAAA